CUCGGUUCCCGGCUCCAGGCGGCGAGCUGAGGUUGGGAGCCUGGCUUUCCCCUCCGAGAGGGUUCAGGUGCCUCUGCCAUAGCUUCUGUCGCCUGUGCUGUGACCCGCACUGGUCGUGGGAGUCACCUGAAAGGCAAGAAAUGGGAGACAGGAAUUGCAGGGAGAAUCAUGCAUCAAUGCCUGGAAAGGUAGAGUCUGUGUUUCCAGUUGGCUGAUGUCUGUUUUAACAUGAAGGUGGGUCAGUGGCUAUGUGGAAACUCCUAAAGGAAGCGGGUAUAAUGAGGCCUGUCCAGAUGUUUCAGGAUUCAGUGGCCUUUGAGGAUGUGGCUGUGACCUUCACCCAAGAGGAGUGGGCUUUGCUGGAUCCUUCCCAGAAAAAUCUCUGUAGAGAUGUGAUGCAAGAAACCUUCAGGAACCUGGCCUCUAUAGGGAAAAAAUGGAAACCCCAGAACAUAUAUGUAGAGUACGAAAAUCUAAGGAGAAACCUAAGAAUUGUGGGAGAGAGACUCUUUGAAAGUAAAGAAGGUCAUCAGCAUGGAGAAAUUUUGACCCAGGUUCCAGAUGACAUGCUGAAGAAAACAACUACUGGAGUAAAAUCAUGCGAAAGCAGUGUGUAUGGAGAAGUAGGCAGUGCUCAUUCAUCUCUUAAUAGGCACAUCAGAGAUGACACUGGACACAAGGCAUAUGAGUAUCAAGAAUAUGGACAGAAACCAUAUAAAUGUAAAUACUGUAAAAAACCUUUCAACUGUCUCUCCUCUGUUCAGACACAUGAAAGGGCUCAUAGUGGAAGGAAACUCUAUGUUUGUGAGGAAUGCGGAAAAACAUUUAUUUCCCAUUCAAACCUUCAAAGACACAGGAUAAUGCACCGUGGAGAUGGACCUUAUAAGUGUAAAUUUUGUGGGAAAGCCUUGAUGUUUCUCAGUUUGUAUCUUAUCCACAAACGAACUCACACUGGAGAGAAACCAUAUCAAUGUAAACAGUGUGGUAAAGCCUUUAGUCAUUCUAGUAGCCUUCGAAUACAUGAAAGAACUCACACUGGGGAGAAGCCUUAUAAAUGUAAUGAAUGUGGGAAAGCAUUCCAUAGUUCCACAUGCCUUCAUGCUCAUAAAAGAACUCACACUGGGGAGAAGCCAUAUGAAUGUAAACAGUGUGGGAAAGCCUUCAGCUCUUCCCAUUCCUUUCAAAUACAUGAAAGAACUCACACGGGGGAGAAGCCAUAUGAAUGUAAGGAAUGUGGAAAAGCAUUCAAGUGUCCCAGUUCUGUUCGCAGACAUGAAAGAACCCACUCUAGGAAAAAACCCUAUGAAUGUAAACAUUGUGGGAAAGUAUUAUCUUAUCUUACCAGCUUUCAAAACCACUUGGGAAUGCACACUGGAGAGAUAUCUCAUAAAUGUAAGAUAUGUGGGAAAGCCUUUUAUUCUCCCAGUUCACUUCAAACACAUGAAAAAACUCACACUGGAGAGAAACCCUAUAAAUGCAACCAAUGUGGUAAAGCCUUUAAUUCUUCCAGUUCCUUCCGAUAUCAUGAAAGAACUCACACUGGAGAGAAACCUUACGAGUGUAAGCAAUGUGGGAAAGCCUUCAGAUCUGCCUCACUCCUUCAAACACAUGGUAGGACUCACACGGGAGAGAAACCCUAUGCAUGUAAGGAAUGUGGAAAACCAUUUAGUAAUUUCUCUUUCUUUCAAAUACAUGAAAGGAUGCACAGAGAAGAGAAGCCGUAUGAAUGUAAGGGUUAUGGGAAAACAUUCAGUUUGCCCAGUUUAUUUCAUAGACAUGAAAGGACUCACACUGGAGGAAAAACCUAUGAAUGCAAGCAGUGUGGCAGAUCCUUCAACUGUUCGAGCUCCUUUCGAUAUCAUGGAAGGACUCACACUGGAGAGAAACCCUAUGAAUGCAAGCAAUGUGGAAAAGCCUUCAGAUCUGCCUCACAGCUUCAAAUUCAUGGAAGGACUCACACUGGAGAGAAACCUUAUGAAUGUAAGCAGUGUGGGAAAGCCUUUGGAUCUGCCUCACACCUUCAAAUGCAUGGAAGGACUCACACUGGAGAGAAACCCUAUGAAUGUAAGCAGUGUGGGAAGUCUUUUGGAUGUGCCUCGCGACUUCAAAUGCAUGGAAGGACUCACACUGGAGAGAAACCGUAUAAAUGUAAGCAAUGUGGGAAAGCUUUUGGAUGUCCCUCAAACCUUCGAAGGCAUGGAAGGACUCACACUGGAGAGAAACCCUAUAAAUGUAACCAAUGUGGUAAAGUCUUUAGAUGUUCUUCACAACUUCAAGUGCAUGGAAGGGCUCACUGCAUAGACACCCCAUAACCCCAGGCUUUAGGAGGCUGAGGUGGGGGGACUGCUUAAGCCCAGGAGUUCAAGACCAGCCUGGGCAACAUAGUGAGACUCUGUUAUAAAAAUUAAAUAAAUAAAUAAAAAGACUUCCAGUUGGUGGUAA